GCGGGUAGGCGCGGGAGCCUCGAGCGCCGCUCGGAUGCAGCAGCCGAGCCGCCACUCGGCGCGCGGCGGGAGACCCAGGGCAAGCCGCCGUCGGCGCGCUGGGUGCGGGAAGGGGGCUCUGGAUUUCGGUCCCUCCCCUUUUUCCUCUGAGUCUCGGAACGCUCCGGCUCUCAGACCCUCUUCCUCCCAGGUAAAGGCCGGGAGAGGAGGGCGCAUCUCUUUUCCAGGCACCCCACCAUGGGCAAUGCCUCCAAUGACUCCCAGUCUGAGGACUGCGAGACGCGACAGUGGCUUCCCCCAGGCGAAAGCCCAGCCAUCAGCUCCGUCAUGUUCUCGGCCGGGGUGCUGGGGAACCUCAUAGCACUGGCGCUGCUGGCGCGCCGCUGGCGGGGGGACGUGGGGUGCAGCGCCGGCCGCAGGAGCUCCCUCUCCUUGUUCCACGUGCUGGUGACCGAGCUGGUGUUCACCGACCUGCUCGGGACCUGCCUCAUCAGCCCAGUGGUACUGGCUUCGUACGCGCGGAACCAGACCCUGGUGGCACUGGCGCCCGAGAGCCGCGCGUGCACCUACUUCGCUUUCGCCAUGACCUUCUUCAGCCUGGCCACGAUGCUCAUGCUCUUCGCCAUGGCCCUGGAGCGCUACCUCUCGAUCGGGCACCCCUACUUCUACCAGCGCCGCGUCUCGCGCUCCGGGGGCCUGGCCGUGCUGCCUGUCAUCUAUGCAGUCUCCCUGCUCUUCUGCUCGCUGCCGCUGCUGGACUAUGGGCAGUACGUCCAGUACUGCCCCGGGACCUGGUGCUUCAUCCGGCACGGGCGGACCGCUUACCUGCAGCUGUACGCCACCCUGCUGCUGCUUCUCAUUGUCUCGGUGCUCGCCUGCAACUUCAGUGUCAUUCUCAACCUCAUCCGCAUGCACCGCCGAAGCCGGAGAAGCCGCUGCGGACCUUCCCUGGGCAGUGGCCGGGGCGGCCCCGGGGCCCGCAGGAGAGGGGAAAGGGUGUCCAUGGCGGAGGAGACGGACCACCUCAUUCUCCUGGCUAUCAUGACCAUCACCUUCGCCGUCUGCUCCUUGCCUUUCACGAUUUUUGCAUAUAUGAAUGAAACCUCUUCCCGAAAGGAAAAAUGGGACCUCCAAGCUCUUAGGUUUUUAUCAAUUAAUUCAAUAAUUGACCCUUGGGUCUUUGCCAUCCUUAGGCCUCCUGUUCUGAGACUAAUGCGUUCAGUCCUCUGUUGUCGGAUUUCAUUAAGAACACAAGAUGCAACACAAACUUCCUGUUCUACACAGUCAGAUGCCAGUAAACAGGCUGACCUUUGAGGUCAGUAGUUUAAAAGUUCUUAGUUAUAUAGCAUCUGGAAGAUCAUUUUGAAAUUGUUCCUUGGAGAAAUGAAAACAGUGUGUAAACAAAAUGAAGCUGCCCUAAUAAAAAGGAGUAUACAAACAUUUAAGCUGUGGUCAAGGCUACAGAUGUGCUGACAAGGCACUUCAUGUAAAGUGUCAGAAGGAGCUACAAAACCUACCCUCAGUGAGCAUGGUACUUGGCCUUUGGAGGAACAAUCGGCUGCAUUGAAGAUCCAGCUGCCUAUUGAUUUAAGCUUUCCUGUUGAAUGACAAAGUAUGUGGUUUUGUAAUUUGUUUGAAACCCCAAACAGUGACUGUACUUUCUAUUUUAAUCUUGCUACUACCGUUAUACACAUAUAGUGUACAGCCAGACCAGAUUAAACUUCAUAUGUAAUCUCUAGGAAGUCAAUAUGUGGAAGCAACCAAGCCUGCUGUCUUGUGAUCACUUAGCGAACCCUUUAUUUGAACAAUGAAGUUGAAAAUCAUAGGCACCUUUUACUGUGAUGUUUGUGUAUGUGGGAGUACUCUCAUCACUACAGUAUUACUCUUACAAGAGUGGACUCAGUGGGUUAACAUCAGUUUUGUUUACUCAUCCUCCAGGAACUGCAGGUCAAGUUGUCAGGUUAUUUAUUUUAUAAUGUCCAUAUGCUAAUAGUGAUCAAGAAGACUUUAGGAAUGGUUCUCUCAACAAGAAAUAAUAGAAAUGUCUCAAGGCAGUUAAUUCUCAUUAAUACUCUUUAUUUAUCCUAUUUCUGGGGGAGGAUGUACGUGGCCAUGUAUGAAGCCAAAUAUUAGGCUUAAAAACUGAAAAAUCUGGUUCAUUCUUCAGAUAUACUGGAACCCUUUUAAAGUUGAUAUUGGGGCCAUGAGUAAAAUAGAUUUUAUAAGAUGACUGUGUUGUACCAAAAUUCAUCUGUCUAUAUUUUAUUUAGGGAACAUGGUUUGACUCAUCUUAUAUGGGAAACCAUGUAGCAGUGAGUCAUAUCUUAAUAUAUUUCUAAAUGUUUGGCAUGUAAAUGUAAACUCAGCAUCAAAAUAUUUCAGUGAAUUUGCACUGUUUAAUCAUAGUUACUGUGUAAACUCAUCUGAAAUGUUACAAAAAUAAACUAUAAAACAAAAA